AUCAGGAUGAGCUUCCAGGCCCCACGCAGACUCCUGGAGCUGGCAGGGCAGAGCCUGCUGAGGGACCAGGCCUUGGCCAUCUCCGUCCUGGAUGAGCUGCCCAGGGAGCUCUUCCCCCCACUGUUCGUGGAGGCCUUCACUAGCAGACGCUGCGAGGUUCUGAAGGUGAUGGUGCAGGCCUGGCCCUUCCCCUGCCUCCCUCUGGGGUCCCUGAUGAAGACGCCUGAUCUGGAGAUCUUACAUUAUGUAGUGGAUGGGAUUGAUUGCCUGCUUGCCCAAAAGGUUCGCCCCAGGAGGUGGAAACUUCAAGUGCUGGAAAUGCGGGAUGUUGAUGAGAAUUUUUGGACCAUAUGGUCUGGAGCCAGGCCCCUGUCCUGCUCCCCAGAGGCCAUGAGUAAGAGACAGACAGUGGAGGACUGUCCAAGGACAGGAGAGAAGCAGCCCUUGAAGGUGUUCAUGGAUGUUUGCCUCAAGGAAAAAUUCAUGGAUGAAGAUCUGAGCUUCUUCUCUGGGUGGGUGCAGCACAGAAGAGGUUCAGUACACCUGUGCUGUACUAAGGUGGUGAAUUAUUCAAUGAGCAUUCUAAAUUUCAGAAACAUAUUGGAAACAGUAUACCCAGACAGUAUCCAAGUGUUGGAAAUUUGGAACAUGUGCUGGCUGUGUAUGAUAGUAGAGUUUAGCCGUUACCUGAGCCAGAUGAGGAAUCUUCGCAAACUCUUCAUCUCCGAUGGCUGUCGUUACCUGCUAAGCUCUGACAGCCAAGAACAGUUAGUUGCUGAAUUCAGCUCUGUGCUCCUCAGGCUGGAGAACCUCCAGAUGCUUUAUGUAAGAAGGGUCUGCUUCUUCAGAGGCCACCUGGACCAGCUGAUCAGGUGCCUCAGGAGCCCGUUGGAGACAUUGGCAUUAACUUAUGGCUUCCUAGAAGAAGAGGACUUGAAAUGCCUGCCCCGGUACCCAAGUCUCAGUCAACUGAAGCAGCUGAAUCUGAGUCAUGGUGCACUGCGCUUCAUCCGUCUUGAGCCCCUCCGAGCUCUGCUAGAGAAAGUUGCUGCCACUCUUCAGACCCUCUUCUUAGUGGACUGUGGGAUUGGGUACUCCAAACUCAGGGUCAUCCUGCCUGCCCUGAGCCGCUGCUCCAACCUCACCACUUUCUGUUUUCACGGCAAUGACACGUCCAUGGAUGCUCUGAAGGACCUGCUGCGCCACACAGGCAGGCUGAGCAAUUUGAGCCUGGAAACAUAUCCUGCCCCUCGGGAGAGUCUUGACAACAGGGGUCGUGUCAUUUUGGAGCUCCUCACCCCACUUCAGGCUGAGCUGAUGCGUAUACUGAGGGAAGUAAGGGAGCCCAAAAGGAUCUUCUUUGGUCCGGUGUCCUGCCCUUGCUGUGGCACUUCGCCCACUGAGCAACUGGAGUUCAAUUUUUGCUUGUGGGGAAGGCCUGCCUAG